CGCACCACUAUACUCCAGCUUGGGCAGCAGAGAGACUGUCUCAAAAAAAAAAAAUCUUCCUGUGGAUUUUGCAGGGUGGCCCAUCAACUGGGCAUGUCCCCAUCCCCCGGCCCUGCUCAGCCACAUCACCGCAGGCACACCGCCACCACACCACCGCUGGCACACUGCUGGCACACCUCCGCCACACCGCGGGCACACUGCUGGCUGGGUGGGGCCGUGUUGGCUGAGGAAGGGCUCUCCUGUGUCCACCGUCAGGCUGUGGUUGUCGGCCCAGCCCAGUCCUGCCUCAGCCCGGCACCCUGAAUGCUGGGAGCUCCACACCCGCCUGCCCCGGGGAGUUCCAGCCUGUCGAGUGUCCACCCCACCAUGGUCAUUGUGCGCAUUUCAUGAGCCGUGUGAGGGAGCCUCCAGUACCCAGGGAGCUGUGUGUCACGCAGCCCAGGCCCAUCCAGCGCCCAUUGGUCAGGGCAAGGCGGGGCCCGGCACAGGGCCUGAGAUGGCGCCAUGGCCUGUACCCAGCUGGGCACCCCAGAGCCUUGGCGGGCGCCAGUGCGUGGGCUGGGUUACGACCCCUACAACCCUGAGCUGCCCAAGCCCCCCGCGCAGAGGGAGAAUGGCACCCUGGGCCUGGGGGAGGAGCCGCGCCCGGAUGUGCUGGAGUUGGAGCUGGUCAACCAGGCCAUCGAGGCCGUGCGCAGUGAGGUGGAGCUGGAGCAGCGGCGCUACCGGGAGCUGCUGGAGACGACCCGUGAGCACCGCUCCGCCGAGGCCCCCGCCCUGGCGCCCCGCGGCCCCAACGCCAGCCCCACUGUGGGCCCGGACGAGGAUGCCUUCCCACUGGCCUUCGACUACAGCCCCGGCAGCCACGGCCUAUUAAGCCCUGAUGCCGGCUACCAGCCCACCCCACUGGCCGCCCCUGCCGAGCCGGGCAGCAAGUACUCGCUGGCGUCCCUGGACAGGGGUCAGGGCAGAGGUGGAGGGGGUGGCGGUGCCCUGGAAUACGUCCCCAAGGCUGUGAGCCAGCCCCGGCGGCACAGCCGCCCCGUUCCCAGUGGCAAGUACGUGGUGGACAACUCCAGGCCACCCACAGACCUGGAGUAUGACCCUCUCUCCAACUACUCGGCCCGGCACCUCAGCAGGGCCAGCUCCCGGGAUGAGCGGGCCGCCAAGCGGCCCCGGGGCUCCCGCGGCAGUGAGCCCUACACACCUGCUCCCAAGAAGCUCUGUGACCCCUUUGGCAGUUGCGAUGCAAGGUUCUCAGACUCAGAAGAUGAGGCCGCCACGGUCCCAGGUAACGAGCCCACCACGGCCAGCACCCCCAAAGCCAGGGCCGACCCUGAGAUCAAGGCCACCGGGCAGCCACCCUCCAAAGAGGGCCUGGAGGCCGAGGGGGGCGGCCUGCGGGAGACCAAGGAGACGGCCGUGCAGUGCGACGUGGGGGACCUCCAGCCGCCCCCAGCCAAGCCCGCCUCCCCAGCCCAGGUCCAGUCCUCACAGGAUGGGGGCUGCCCCAAGGAGGGAAAACCCAAGAAGAAAAAAACCGGGGCCCCACCUGCCCCCAGCUGCAAAGACGGGGCCCAGGGGAAGGACAAGACCAAGGACAAGGGCCGAGGGCGGCCUGUGGAGAAGCCCCGUGCGGACAAGAAGGGCCCGCAGGCCAGCAGCCCCCGGCGCAAGGCAGAGCGGCCGGAAGGGACCAAGAAGAAGCCAUCUUCGGCCACUCCUGUGGCCACCUCAGGGAAAGGGAGGCCUGACCGGCCAGCGCGGCGGCCGAGCCCCACAAGCGGGGACUCCCGACCGGCGGCCGGCAGAGGCCCACCCCGCCCCCUCCAGCUGCCCGACAGGAAGAGCACCAAGGCCCCGUCGGGGAAGCUAGUGGAGCGGAAAGCCCGCUCACUAGACGAGGGCGCCUCCCAGGACGCCCCCAAGCUGAAGAAGCGGGCCCUGAGCCACGCCGACCUCUUUGGGGACGAGAGUGAGGACGAGGCCGCAGGGCCAGGGGUGCCGAGCGUGUGGCCCUCUGCCCUCCCCAGCCUCAGCUCGGACUCAGACUCCGACUCAGACUCCAGCCUGGGCUUCCCGGAGGCGCAGGGGCCGCCCAAGCGGCUCAAGGCCUCCCCGCCCCCCUCCCCCGCCCCAUCCUCCUCCUCCUCCUCCUCCUCCUCCACCUCCAGCGCGGGGGCGGAUGUGGACUACUCGGCCCUGGAGAAGGAGGUGGACUUUGACUCCGACCCCAUGGAGGAGUGCCUGCGGAUCUUCAACGAGUCCACCAGCGUCAAGACGGAGGACAGAGGCCGGCUGGCCCGGCAGCCCCCCAAGGAAGAGAAGAGUGAGGAGAAGGGGCUUUCGGGUCUGACCACUCUGUUCCCCGGGCAGAAGAGGAGGAUCUCCCACCUUUCCAAGCAAGGCCAGGAGGUGGAGCCCCCGAGGAGGGGUCCCGCGGUGCCCCCGGCCCGGCCCCCGACGGCGCAGGAGGUGUGCUACCUGCGGGCCCAGCAGGCGCAGAGGGCAUCGGCGAGCUUGCUGCAGGCCCCCGCCAGGCUGGCAGAGAAGUCGCCCUCCGUCCACAUUUCCGCCCCUGGCGAGAAGAGGAGGAUCGCCCACAUCCCCAACCCCCGCCUGGCUGCAGCCCCCACAGGUGCCAAGAGGACCCUUGCGGCCAGCGGCAGCCAGUCCUCCAACGGCCCUGAGCCAGGUGGCCAGCAGCUGAAAACACGCACAUUGUCGGGGAUGGCGUCCAAGACUACCACCACCAUCAUCCCUAAGCGAAUCGCCCACAGUCCAUCCUUACAGAGUUUAAAGAAACCCAUUAUCCCCAAAGAGUUUGGGGGCAAAGUCCCCACCGUCAUCCGCCAGCGCUAUCUCAACCUGUUCAUCGAGGAGUGUCUCAAGUUCUGUACCUCCAACCAGGAGGCCAUAGAGAAGGCACUGAACGAGGAGAAGGUGGCCUAUGACCGCAGCCCCAGCAAGAACAUCUACCUGAAUGUGGCCGUGAACACCCUCAAGAAGCUCAGGGGCCUGGCCCCCAGCGCUGUGCCCGGCCUCAGCAAAACCAGUGGCCGCAGGGUUGUGUCCCACGAGGUGGUGUUGGGGGGCAGGUUGGCCGCCAAGACCAGCUUCUCGCUCAGCCGUCCAAGCAGCCCCCGGGUGGAGGACCUGAAAGGGGCUGCCCUGUACAGCCGCCUCAGGGAGUACCUGCUCACCCAGGACCAGCUCAAGGAGAACGGCUACCCCUUCCCGCACCCAGAGCGGCCCGGGGGCGCAAUCAUCUUCACAGCUGAGGAGAAGAGGCCCAAGGACUGUGAGUCGCUGGCCUGCGACGGCCUAGCUUCCUGCAGGACCUGCUGCCGCUGUGGCACCGAGUACCUCGUGUCCUCUUCAGGCCGCUGCAUCCGGGACGAGGAGUGUUAUUACCACUGGGGACGGCUGCGCCGGAACCGGGUGGCCGGAGGCUGGGAGACCCAGUACAUGUGCUGCUCGGCUGCCGCCGGCUCUGUCGGCUGCCAAGUCGCAAAGCAACACGUGCAGGAUGGCCGGAAGGAGCGCCUUGAGGGCUUCGUGAAGACCUUUGAGAAAGAGCUCUCAGGAGACACCCACCCGGGGAUCUACGCCCUGGACUGCGAGAUGUCCUACACCACAUAUGGCCUGGAGCUGACGCGCGUCACGGUGGUCGACACGGACGUGCACGUGGUUUAUGACACCUUCGUGAAGCCUGACAACGAGAUCGUGGACUACAACACCAGGUUUUCGGGGGUGACGGAGGCUGACCUUGCCGACACAAGUGUCACGCUGCGUGACGUCCAGGCCGUUCUGCUGAGCAUGUUCAGCGCUGACACCAUCCUCAUCGGACACAGCCUGGAGAGCGACCUCCUGGCCCUGAAGGUCAUCCACAGCACCGUGGUGGACACGUCUGUGCUCUUCCCCCACCGCCUGGGCCUCCCCUACAAGCGGUCCCUGCGGAACCUCAUGGCCGACUACCUCAGACAGAUCAUCCAGGACAAUGGUGAGUGCCGGUGCCUGCCCUGGGGCCGUCCCUGCGCAGGGGCCGGGUGCUCACCGCAUCUGCCCCGCAGUGGAUGGGCACAGCUCCAGCGAGGACGCCGGCGCCUGCAUGCACCUGGUGAUCUGGAAGGUUCGAGAAGACGCCAAGACCAAGCGAUGACGCCUGCCCGCCUCCCACCCGCCUCUCCUGCCGUCCCGCUGGUCCUUAGCCCCAUGCCUCUUCCAAAACAGUGCAAUAAAUCUCCGGUAACCCGUCCACCUGGCCGAGGCAGCCCAGAGCAGCGGGAUGAGCUGGCGGCCAGAGAACGCCCAGCCCAGCCCACCCCCGCUCACGUCCUGCCGCACCCCUCCGCCGGUCCCCACCCUCUGCCCCCCAGCCCUCUGGCGUCUCUAGAAACUGCUGCUGAUGGAGACCAGGACAGAGCCCGCCCCCACCCGGCCCGCAGCCCCUCCUGCCCCUCCUGCCAGGCCCUCCCUCCCGGGUGGUGGCCGGCACCUCUGCUCCUCACGUGGGUCGCGGGGCGGGCUUGUCCCAGGUUUGUUUGAGACAGUCUUUUUUUAUUUUGUAUUGUUAUUUUUAUUAUUUUUAAUUUAAACCUGAUGACUUGCACAGCAUCUUUCCCACCGGGAAGAGCGGGCCUGCUGCCUUCCCUCCUGCGGGGUGGGGGUGGGACAGACCCCAGUGGGGGCCAGGGCCACACUCAGCGCAGUGUGGGCUGGACCCGCCUCUGUGCUCCAGGGGCUGGCCGGUCUUCGGGGGCGCCGGCUUCCACCACUCGCCGCCCCACCCCUGCACUCCGUGACCUCUGAGAACCCAGCUGGCCCCUCGUUAGCCCCAGGGUCUGCCGUCUAGAGGGAGCCCACCGGCCUCCGGACACUGUCUUCCCGCUAGAGCCCCGUCCUCCUCUGCGGGGCUCUCCGGACCCCCUUCCCCCUCACCUCCAGGCAGGGACAGAAUAAAUGUUUGUAUGGAUUUUA